AGCUGCCACUGCUGUAGCUUCUGCCACCUGCCACGACCGGGCCUCUCCCUGGCGUUUGGUCACCUCUGCUUCAUUCUCCACCGCGCCUAUGGUCCCUCUUGGAGCCAGCGUGGCGGGCCUGGCGGCUCCCGGGUGGUGAGAGAGCGGUCCGGGAACGAUGAAGGCCUCGCAGUGCUGCUGCUGUCUCAGCCACCUCUUGGCUUCCGUCCUCCUCCUGCUGUUGCUGCCUGAACUAAGCGGGCCCCUGGCAGUCCUGCUGCAGGCAGCCGAGGCCGCGCCAGGUCUUGGGCCUCCUGACCCUAGACCACGGACAUUACCGCCGCUGCCACCGGGCCCUACCCCUGCCCAGCAGCCGGGCCGUGGUCUGGCUGAAGCUGCGGGGCCGCGGGGCUCCGAGGGAGGCAAUGGCAGCAACCCUGUGGCCGGGCUUGAGACGGACGAUCACGGAGGGAAGGCCGGGGAAGGCUCGGUGGGUGGCGGCCUUGCUGUGAGCCCCAACCCUGGCGACAAGCCCAUGACCCAGCGGGCCCUGACCGUGUUGAUGGUGGUGAGCGGCGCGGUGCUGGUGUACUUCGUGGUCAGGACGGUCAGGAUGAGAAGAAGAAACCGAAAGACUAGGAGAUAUGGAGUUUUGGACACUAACAUAGAAAAUAUGGAAUUGACACCUUUAGAACAGGAUGAUGAGGAUGAUGACAACACGUUGUUUGAUGCCAAUCAUCCUCGAAGACUGCUGUGGAAUUCCUGAGAAAGAGCAACUGAGGGAUAGCAACAUGGAUUUCACUGAAUAAGAAUGUGCCUUUUGAUGAAAGAACUUUAUCUUUCUACAAUGAAGAGUGGAAUUUCUAUGUUUAAGGAAUAAGAAGCCACUAUAUCAAUGUUGGGGGGGUAUUUAAGUUACAUAUAUUUUAACAACCUUUAAUUUGCUGUUGCAAUAAAUACCGUAUCCUUUUAUUAUAUCUUUAUAUGUAUAGAAGUACUCUGUUAAUGGGCUCAGAGAUGUUGGGGAUAAAGUAUACUGUAAUAAUUUAUCUGUUUGAAAAUUACUAUAAAACGGUGUUUUCUGAUCGGUUUUUGUUUCCUGCUUACCAUAUGAUUGUAAAUUGUUUUAUGUAUUAAUCAGUUAAUGCUAAUUAUUUUUGCUGAUGUCAUAUGUUAAAGAGCUAUAAAUUCCAACAACCAACUGGUGUGUAAAAAUAAUUUAAAAUUUCCUUUACUGAAAGGUAUUUCCCAUUUUUGUGGGGAAAAGAAGCCAAAUUUAUUACUUUGUGUUGGGGUUUUUAAAAUAUUAAGAAAUGUCUAAGUUAUUGUUUGCAAAACAAUAAAUAUGAUUUUAAAUUCUCUUAAA